UCGCCUUCCGGAUACCGGAAAUGGGAUAUUCGCGGCCCGAGCAUCUGCUCGGGAUUAGACUUGGCGGGCACGGGGAGAACUAGACCUCAAGGAGGGGGUUCCGCCUGUGCUUAGGUACGACCCUGGAGGUGCCGCGCAACGCAGUAGUGACCUCCCAAAAUCCAGACACCGGAUUUUGUUUAGAAGAGUGCUUGUACAAAGCCCUAGUGUUAGAACUGGUCAUGGUCUUCUAAGCGGCCGAGUCGUUGGCCCAUAAGCACGUAUCGGAUGGCUUCCAUGUAAAUCAGGGCUUAGGUGACUUCCUGCUGGCCUUCAGGGGUGAGCGUCACGCGUCAAGGGCGGUUCGUGCGUGUGCAGGGCUUGCUAAGUCGCAGGAAAUGGGAGGUCGCAGCACGCCGCUACCUGCAAGCCCGAAAGCUGAAUGCAGCUCUAGUGUGGCGCGUAGUCUUACUGGGUACUAUUUUACUUAAUCGCUGACGUUGAGUGAGAGGUGACCAAGCUCAGAUGCUGAGAUUAAGGCGGCCGGGCGAAACUCGCGACACCCUGCGAUUCCCUCUUAGCCAGCUGCGUAAAGUUGCCUACGCCAAGCGGGUAGCGUCCUGCUCGGCCACCUGGCGGCGGGCGUGGAGUUGGCAGGCAGGCAGUGGGGGUCACGCCGGCAUGAAAGGCCAGAUCACCUGCAGGUCGCCAAGUUGCCGGGAAUCCCCCGCUCCGAGCAGUGUCAUGCCCAUCACAAAUAACCCUAUCGCAGCCGGGAGGAAGGCUCCCCUGUUCCUUUUUGCUGACGUGUCAUUUCUAAGUACUUUCUCCUACUCCAUAAAGACUUCAAGAAGCCAUGGCAGCAUGUCCGUAUGCUGGUGGAAUCAUCAAGUAGAGAGAGAAGAAUUGAUGCUGCAUUAGAGAGAGGGAGCAAUUGCAGGAACAAUGUGUUGAGUGGGAGAGAUGGGAUGCCAUCCAGAUGCAGAUGGAGGCGUUGAUCUUAAACAAGCAGGGAUGGAUCCAUCACUGAAGCAAGAGGAAAGGAGAAGACAGAAGUAUAGAUGCACAAAGUAAGUAACUGGAAUGUCUCAAUAAAAUGAUUCUUGGACUGGGUGUAAAA